AGAUACGUUCGUCAGCUUGCUCCUUUCUGCCCGUGGACGCCGCCGAAGAAGCAUCGUUAAAGUCUCUCUUCACCCUGCCGUCAUGUCUAAGUCAGAGUCUCCUAAAGAGCCCGAACAGCUGAGGAAGCUCUUCAUUGGAGGGUUGAGCUUUGAAACAACUGAUGAGAGCCUGAGGAGCCAUUUUGAGCAAUGGGGAACGCUCACGGACUGUGUGGUAAUGAGAGAUCCAAACACCAAGCGCUCCAGGGGCUUUGGGUUUGUCACAUAUGCCACUGUGGAGGAGGUGGAUGCAGCUAUGAAUGCAAGGCCACACAAGGUGGAUGGAAGAGUUGUGGAACCAAAGAGAGCUGUCUCCAGAGAAGAUUCUCAAAGACCAGGUGCCCACUUAACUGUGAAAAAGAUAUUUGUUGGUGGCAUUAAAGAAGACACUGAAGAACAUCACCUAAGAGAUUAUUUUGAACAGUAUGGAAAAAUUGAAGUGAUUGAAAUCAUGACUGACCGAGGCAGUGGCAAGAAAAGGGGCUUUGCCUUUGUAACCUUUGACGACCAUGACUCCGUGGAUAAGAUUGUCAUUCAGAAAUACCAUACUGUGAAUGGCCACAACUGUGAAGUUAGAAAAGCCCUGUCAAAGCAAGAGAUGGCUAGUGCUUCAUCCAGCCAAAGAGGUCGAAGUGGUUCUGGAAACUUUGGUGGUGGUCGUGGAGGUGGUUUCGGUGGGAAUGACAACUUCGGUCGUGGAGGAAACUUCAGUGGUCGUGGUGGCUUUGGUGGCAGCCGUGGUGGUGGUGGAUAUGGUGGCAGUGGGGAUGGCUAUAAUGGAUUUGGUAAUGAUGGUGGUUAUGGAGGAGGCGGCCCUGGUUACUCUGGAGGAAGCAGAGGCUAUGGAAGUGGUGGACAGGGUUAUGGAAACCAGGGCAGUGGCUAUGGCGGGAGUGGCAGCUAUGACAGCUAUAACAACGGAGGCGGAGGCGGCUUUGGCGGUGGUAGUGGAAGCAAUUUUGGAGGUGGUGGAAGCUACAAUGAUUUUGGGAAUUACAACAAUCAGUCUUCAAAUUUUGGACCCAUGAAGGGAGGAAAUUUUGGAGGCAGAAGCUCUGGCCCCUAUGGCGGUGGAGGCCAAUACUUUGCAAAACCACGAAACCAAGGUGGCUAUGGCGGUUCCAGCAGCAGCAGUAGCUAUGGCAGUGGCAGAAGAUUUUAAUUAGGAAACAAAGCUUAGCAGGAGAGGAGAGCCAGAGAAGUGACAGGGAAGCUACAGGUUACAACAGAUUUGUGAACUCAGCCAAGCACAGUGGUGGCAGGGCCUAGCUGCUACAAAGAAGACAUGUUUUAGACAAAUACUCAUGUGUAUGGGCAAAAAACUCGAGGACUGUAUUUGUGACUAAUUGUAUAACAGGUUAUUUUAGUUUCUGUUCUGUGGAAAGUGUAAAGCAUUCCAACAAAGGGUUUUAAUGUAGAUUUUUUUUUUUGCACCCCAUGCUGUUGAUUGCUAAAUGUAACAGUCUGAUCGUGACGCUGAAUAAAUGUCUUUUUUUUAAUGUGCUGUGUAAAGUUAGUCUACUCUUAAGCCAUCUUGGUAAAUUUCCCCAACAGUGUGAAGUUAGAAUUCCUUCAGGGUGAUGCCAGGUUCUAUUUGGAAUUUAUAUACAACCUGCUUGGGUGGAGAAGCCAUUGUCUUCGGAAACCUUGGUGUAGUUGAACUGAUAGUUACUGUUGUGACCUGAAGUUCACCAUUAAAAGGGAUUACCCAAGCAAAAUCAUGGAAUGGUUAUAAAAGUGAUUGUUGGCACAUCCUAUGCAAUAUAUCUAAAUUGAAUAAUGGUACCAGAUAAAAUUAUAGAUGGGAAUGAAGCUUGUGUAUCCAUUAUCAUGUGUAAUCAAUAAACGAUUUAAUUCUCUUGAAUGAAAUGACAACUGUAUGGAUUUGGGACUGGCAGAGAUUUGGACUUUCCCUACCCACUCCCCCUGAUAAUAAUGUUGAAUGCUUCUAUCACAAUUCAAGUUCAAAGCUCUGCCAGGGAAUAGAAACUAGCUGCUGGCUAAUGCCGCUCCAUAAAUCCGCAGAUUUGAAGUGUCUGGGAGGCCUUUUAAAAAUAACUAAUAUCAGAAAGCAUUUUAAUGAACGUAAAGAUAGGCUUACAUUAAAGGAAAACUGCAGUUUGACUGGGUUCUGGUUGGGUGGGCCUUCAGAGGUUCUAUCAGUUAACUAUACUAAUUAAUUUGGAGAUUCAAACCAUACCAAUAGAAACUAAAUUUUUCUACAUAAUUUCAUGUUAACUGCAGUUUCCCUUUAUGGCACAAGGGGUCACACAACCUACCUAAAAUGUUAAUUGUAUAGAAAAUGAUUUCUAAACCUUUAACAGUUAAUAUCCAAUAAUGUGUUAUUUGUACAUAGAUUCUUUUGAGCCUUACCUUUGGUGCUCUCUCAAUUUCAGUGCUAUUGUACCUAGUAGCAUAGAGAUUUGUCUAUCAAUAGGACUGUAUAUUCCAUCCCAUGGGUGUGUUGGAAGUUUGGGGAGGAGGAGGGUGGUGGGAGGUGGGUGGGAGGUGGUGGUGGGUGGGAAAGCAUGGGUGAUAGUUCCAUGAUACUGGCUGAGUUUGCAAUAGCAGGUGGAACCCUAACUAUUGAGGGAGUUUGCAGAUACCUCAGGAUUCGUGACAAUGCCUUUAAAGAUCCAGGAGAGAUGUUCAGCUACUAGGAACUGCUAGCAAGUAUAGCGCGAAUGGCUCCGAGCUCAGACACUCUACAGCUGAGAGUAGACACUUGUGGUAUGUGGAGUACAGAUAAGCCAGGGGCAGGCCACGGCACGCUCCAUGAAAGCUAGGAGGGAGUGAAAUAUCAGUGAUCAUCGCAAGGAAGGAGGCAGACAAGAGUAAGGCACACCUGACUCUUAGGACUAGCAGUCAGAACCAGGAGGAAAGGUUUUAUUGCUAUGCGGGUAGGUAAGAACAGAUUUUACUUACAUCCAUAUAGUUACUUAAAGUCCAGUUUUCUGUUAAACAUUUUUCUUAAUAUAUUGAGCCAAAACUAGUCCAGUUAAGCUGAACUUGGUUUUUCUGGAGAUGAAUUGUUUUAAAUUGACACCCUAUUGAUGGCUCCCAGUUGAAGGAAGUGAGCACAUUAUUUGUACUGUGAAUAUAAAUUUUUGCCCUUUUAUUUAUCUUCCUUUGACCCAUUUCCUUAAAAUAAUGGCUCAAAGUAAUAGACUUCCCCAAAUGGUGGGGGGAUGGGUGGGUUAUUAAUGGGAGGUAUGGGGGGUUUAGCUUGAGAUGGGACUUGGUCUUAGAGCUAGUUCUAAAGGUUGUUUACUUUUCUAGGGAGGAGUCUGCUACUAGUCUUAUCAGCUCUUAAAAACAGAAACUCAUCUGUCCAAGUUCGUGGCAGAAAGGUAAGUUUUUACAAAUUAGUGCUCAGCAAAAGAAUGCCCUGCGUUCCCAAAGUAAAAGAAUGACAAGCUGUACCUUAAACCAAAACACUUCGUAAUCUCAUCCAAUUGCAAAAAGAGUUAUUAGCCAACCAGGUAUUCCCAGUAGUGACAGUGGAUAUAACUGUGUAGUCAUUCACCUCUGCUUAUAUGAAUACUUUACAACCUCUUUUGCCUUUUGCAGGAACGUCCUUGUGAAGACCUUUAUCUGAGCCACUGUACUUCGUUAUCACUGCCAUGCAGUUUACAUGAGCUGUUCUGCAGCUCAAAUUCCAUUUUGUGAAUGGGUUUUUUUUUUUAAUAAACUGUAUUUAACUUA